GAGCUCCUCUGCUACUCAGAGUUGCAACCUCAGCCUCGCUAUGGCUCCCAGCAGCCCCCGGCCCGCGCUGCCCGCACUCCUGGUCCUGCUCGGGGCUCUGUUCCCAGGACCUGGCAAUGCCCAGACAUCUGUGUCCCCCUCAAAAGUCAUCCUGCCCCGGGGAGGCUCCGUGCUGGUGACAUGCAGCACCUCCUGUGACCAGCCCAAGUUGUUGGGCAUAGAGACCCCGUUGCCUAAAAAGGAGUUGCUCCUGCCUGGGAACAACCGGAAGGUGUAUGAACUGAGCAAUGUGCAAGAAGAUAGCCAACCAAUGUGCUAUUCAAACUGCCCUGAUGGGCAGUCAACAGCUAAAACCUUCCUCACCGUGUACUGGACUCCAGAACGGGUGGAACUGGCACCCCUCCCCUCUUGGCAGCCAGUGGGCAAGAACCUUACCCUACGCUGCCAGGUGGAGGGUGGGGCACCCCGGGCCAACCUCACCGUGGUGCUGCUCCGUGGGGAGAAGGAGCUGAAACGGGAGCCAGCUGUGGGGGAGCCCGCUGAGGUCACGACCACGGUGCUGGUGAGGAGAGAUCACCAUGGAGCCAAUUUCUCGUGCCGCACUGAACUGGACCUGCGGCCCCAAGGGCUGGAGCUGUUUGAGAACACCUCGGCCCCCUACCAGCUCCAGACCUUUGUCCUGCCAGCGACUCCCCCACAACUUGUCAGCCCCCGGGUCCUAGAGGUGGACACGCAGGGGACCGUGGUCUGUUCCCUGGACGGGCUGUUCCCAGUCUCGGAGGCCCAGGUCCACCUGGCACUGGGGGACCAGAGGUUGAACCCCACAGUCACCUAUGGCAACGACUCCUUCUCGGCCAAGGCCUCAGUCAGUGUGACCGCAGAGGACGAGGGCACCCAGCGGCUGACGUGUGCAGUAAUACUGGGGAACCAGAGCCAGGAGACACUGCAGACAGUGACCAUCUACAGCUUUCCGGCGCCCAACGUGAUUCUGACGAAGCCAGAGGUCUCAGAAGGGACCGAGGUGACAGUGAAGUGUGAGGCCCACCCUAGAGCCAAGGUGACGCUGAAUGGGGUUCCAGCCCAGCCACUGGGCCCGAGGGCCCAGCUCCUGCUGAAGGCCACCCCAGAGGACAACGGGCGCAGCUUCUCCUGCUCUGCAACCCUGGAGGUGGCCGGCCAGCUUAUACACAAGAACCAGACCCGGGAGCUUCGUGUCCUGUAUGGCCCCCGACUGGACGAGAGGGAUUGUCCGGGAAACUGGACGUGGCCAGAAAAUUCCCAGCAGACUCCAAUGUGCCAGGCUUGGGGGAACCCAUUGCCCGAGCUCAAGUGUCUAAAGGAUGGCACUUUCCCACUGCCCAUCGGGGAAUCAGUGACUGUCACUCGAGAUCUUGAGGGCACCUACCUCUGUCGGGCCAGGAGCACUCAAGGGGAGGUCACCCGCAAGGUGACCGUGAAUGUGCUCUCCCCCCGGUAUGAGAUUGUCAUCAUCACUGUGGUAGCAGCCGCAGUCAUAAUGGGCACUGCAGGCCUCAGCACGUACCUCUAUAACCGCCAGCGGAAGAUCAAGAAAUACAGACUACAACAGGCCCAAAAAGGGACCCCCAUGAAACCGAACACACAAGCCACGCCUCCCUGAACCUAUCCCGGGACAGGGCCUCUUCCUCGGCCUUCCCAUAUUGGUGGCAGUGGUGCCACACUGAACAGAGUGGAAGACAUAUGCCAUGCAGCUACACCUACCGGCCCUGGGACGCCGGAGGACAGGGCAUUGUCCUCAGUCAGAUACAACAGCAUUUGGGGCCAUGGUACCUGCACACCUAAAACACUAGGCCACGCAUCUGAUCUGUAGUCACAUGACUAAGCCAAGAGGAAGGAGCAAGACUCAAGACAUGAUUGAUGGAUGUUAAAGUCUAGCCUGAUGAGAGGGGAAGUGGUGGGGGAGACAUAGCCCCACCAUGAGGACAUACAACUGGGAAAUACUGAAACUUGCUGCCUAUUGGGUAUGCUGAGGCCCCACAGACUUACAGAAGAAGUGGCCCUCCAUAGACAUGUGUAGCAUCAAAACACAAAGGCCCACACUUCCUGACGGAUGCCAGCUUGGGCACUGCUGUCUACUGACCCCAACCCUUGAUGAUAUGUAUUUAUUCAUUUGUUAUUUUACCAGCUAUUUAUUGAGUGUCUUUUAUGUAGGCUAAAUGAACAUAGGUCUCUGGCCUCACGGAGCUCCCAGUCCUAAUCACAUUCAAGGUCACCAGGUACAGUUGUACAGGUUGUACACUGCAGGAGAGUGCCUGGCAAAAAGAUCAAAUGGGGCUGGGACUUCUCAUUGGCCAACCUGCCUUUCCCCAGAAGGAGUGAUUUUUCUAUCGGCACAAAAGCACUAUAUGGACUGGUAAUGGUUACAGGUUCAGAGAUUACCCAGUGAGGCCUUAUUCCUCCCUUCCCCCCAAAACUGACACCUUUGUUAGCCACCUCCCCACCCACAUACAUUUCUGCCAGUGUUCACAAUGACACUCAGCGGUCAUGUCUGGACAUGAGUGCCCAGGGAAUAUGCCCAAGCUAUGCCUUGUCCUCUUGUCCUGUUUGCAUUUCACUGGGAGCUUGCACUAUGCAGCUCCAGUUUCCUGCAGUGAUCAGGGUCCUGCAAGCAGUGGGGAAGGGGGCCAAGGUAUUGGAGGACUCCCUCCCAGCUUUGGAAGCCUCAUCCGCGUGUGUGUGUGUGUGUAUGUGUAGACAAGCUCUCGCUCUGUCACCCAGGCUGGAGUGCAGUGGUGCAAUCAUGGUUCACUGCAGUCUUGACCUUUUGGGCUCAAGUGAUCCUCCCACCUCAGCCUCCUGAGUAGCUGGGACCAUAGGCUCACAACACCACACCUGGCAAAUUUGAUUUUUUUUUUUUUUCCAGAGACGGGGUCUCGCAACAUUGCCCAGACUUCCUUUGUGUUAGUUAAUAAAGCUUUCUCAACUGCC